AGCGCCCCCUCCGAGAUCCCGGGGAGCCAGCUUGCUGGGAGAGCGGGACGGUCCGGAGCAAGCCCAGAGGCAGAGGAGGCGACAGAGGGAAAAAGGGCCGAGCUAGCCGCUCCAGUGCUGUACAGGAGCCGAAGGGACGCACCACGCCAGCCCCAGCCCGGCUCCAGCGACAGCCAACGCCUCUUGCAGCGCGGCGGCUUCGAAGCCGCCGCCCGGAGCUGCCCUUUCCUCUUCGGUGAAGUUUUUAAAAGCUGCUAAAGACUCGGAGGAAGCAAGGAAAGUGCCUGGUAGGACUGACGGCUGCCUUUGUCCUCCUCCUCUCCACCCCGCCUCCCCCCACCCUGCCUUCCCCCCCUCCCCCGUCUUCUCUCCCGCAGCUGCCUCAGUCGGCUACUCUCAGCCAACCCCCCUCACCACCCUUCUCCCCACCCGCCCCCCCGCCCCCGUCGGCCCAGCGCUGCCAGCCCGAGUUUGCAGAGAGGUAACUCCCUUUGGCUGCGAGCGGGCGAGCUAGCUGCACAUUGCAAAGAAGGCUCUUAGGAGCCAGGCGACUGGGGAGCGGCUUCAGCACUGCAGCCACGACCCGCCUGGUUAGGCUGCACGCGGAGAGAACCCUCUGUUUUCCCCCACUCUCUCUCCACCUCCUCCUGCCUUCCCCACCCCGAGUGCGGAGCCAGAGAUCAAAAGAUGAAAAGGCAGUCAGGUCUUCAGUAGCCAAAAAACAAAACAAACAAAAACAAAAAAGCCGAAAUAAAAGAAAAAGAUAAUAACUCAGUUCUUAUUUGCACCUACUUCAGUGGACACUGAAUUUGGAAGGUGGAGGAUUUUGUUUUUUUCUUUUAAGAUCUGGGCAUCUUUUGAAUCUACCCUUCAAGUAUUAAGAGACAGACUGUGAGCCUAGCAGGGCAGAUCUUGUCCACCGUGUGUCUUCUUCUGCACGAGACUUUGAGGCUGUCAGAGCGCUUUUUGCGUGGUUGCUCCCGCAAGUUUCCUUCUCUGGAGCUUCCCGCAGGUGGGCAGCUAGCUGCAGCGACUACCGCAUCAUCACAGCCUGUUGAACUCUUCUGAGCAAGAGAAGGGGAGGCGGGGUAAGGGAAGUAGGUGGAAGAUUCAGCCAAGCUCAAGGAUGGAAGUGCAGUUAGGGCUGGGAAGGGUCUACCCUCGGCCGCCGUCCAAGACCUACCGAGGAGCUUUCCAGAAUCUGUUCCAGAGCGUGCGCGAAGUGAUCCAGAACCCGGGCCCCAGGCACCCAGAGGCCGCGAGCGCAGCACCUCCCGGCGCCAGUUUGCUGCUGCUGCAGCAGCAGCAGCAGCAGCAGCAGCAGCAGCAGCAGCAGCAGCAGCAGCAGCAGCAGCAGCAGCAGCAAGAGACUAGCCCCAGGCAGCAGCAGCAGCAGCAGGGUGAGGAUGGUUCUCCCCAAGCCCAUCGUAGAGGCCCCACAGGCUACCUGGUCCUGGAUGAGGAACAGCAACCUUCACAGCCGCAGUCGGCCCUGGAGUGCCACCCCGAGAGAGGUUGCGUCCCAGAGCCUGGAGCCGCCGUGGCCGCCAGCAAGGGGCUGCCGCAGCAGCUGCCAGCACCUCCGGACGAGGAUGACUCAGCUGCCCCAUCCACGUUGUCCCUGCUGGGCCCCACUUUCCCCGGCUUAAGCAGCUGCUCCGCUGACCUUAAAGACAUCCUGAGCGAGGCCAGCACCAUGCAACUCCUUCAGCAACAGCAGCAGGAAGCAGUAUCCGAAGGCAGCAGCAGCGGGAGAGCGAGGGAGGCCUCGGGGGCUCCCACUUCCUCCAAGGACAAUUACUUAGGGGGCACUUCGACCAUUUCUGACAACGCCAAGGAGUUGUGUAAGGCAGUGUCGGUGUCCAUGGGCCUGGGUGUGGAGGCGUUGGAGCAUCUGAGUCCAGGGGAACAGCUUCGGGGGGAUUGCAUGUACGCCCCACUUUUGGGAGUUCCACCCGCUGUGCGUCCCACUCCUUGUGCCCCAUUGGCCGAAUGCAAAGGUUCUCUGCUAGACGACAGCGCAGGCAAGAGCACUGAAGAUACUGCUGAGUAUUCCCCUUUCAAGGGAGGUUACACCAAAGGGCUAGAAGGCGAGAGCCUAGGCUGCUCUGGCAGCGCUGCAGCAGGGAGCUCCGGGACACUUGAACUGCCGUCUACCCUGUCUCUCUACAAGUCCGGAGCACUGGACGAGGCAGCUGCGUACCAGAGUCGCGACUACUACAACUUUCCACUGGCUCUGGCCGGACCGCCGCCCCCUCCGCCGCCUCCCCAUCCCCACGCUCGCAUCAAGCUGGAGAACCCGCUGGACUACGGCAGCGCCUGGGCGGCUGCGGCGGCGCAGUGCCGCUAUGGGGACCUGGCGAGCCUGCAUGGCGCGGGUGCAGCGGGACCCGGUUCUGGGUCACCCUCAGCCGCCGCUUCCUCAUCCUGGCACACUCUCUUCACAGCCGAAGAAGGCCAGUUGUAUGGACCGUGUGGUGGUGGUGGGGGUGGUGGCGGCGGCGGCGGCGGCGGCGGCGGCGGCGGCGGCGGCGGCGGCGGCGGCGAGGCGGGAGCUGUAGCCCCCUACGGCUACACUCGGCCCCCUCAGGGGCUGGCGGGCCAGGAAAGCGACUUCACCGCACCUGAUGUGUGGUACCCUGGCGGCAUGGUGAGCAGAGUGCCCUAUCCCAGUCCCACUUGUGUCAAAAGCGAAAUGGGCCCCUGGAUGGAUAGCUACUCCGGACCUUACGGGGACAUGCGUUUGGAGACUGCCAGGGACCAUGUUUUGCCCAUUGACUAUUACUUUCCACCCCAGAAGACCUGCCUGAUCUGUGGAGAUGAAGCUUCUGGGUGUCACUAUGGAGCUCUCACAUGUGGAAGCUGCAAGGUCUUCUUCAAAAGAGCCGCUGAAGGGAAACAGAAGUACCUGUGCGCCAGCAGAAAUGAUUGCACUAUUGAUAAAUUCCGAAGGAAAAAUUGUCCAUCUUGUCGUCUUCGGAAAUGUUAUGAAGCAGGGAUGACUCUGGGAGCCCGGAAGCUGAAGAAACUUGGUAAUCUGAAACUACAGGAGGAAGGAGAGGCUUCCAGCACCACCAGCCCCACUGAGGAGACAACCCAGAAGCUGACAGUGUCACACAUUGAAGGCUAUGAAUGUCAGCCCAUCUUUCUGAAUGUCCUGGAAGCCAUUGAGCCAGGUGUAGUGUGUGCUGGACACGACAACAACCAGCCCGACUCCUUUGCAGCCUUGCUCUCUAGCCUCAAUGAACUGGGAGAGAGACAGCUUGUACACGUGGUCAAGUGGGCCAAGGCCUUGCCUGGCUUCCGCAACUUACACGUGGACGACCAGAUGGCUGUCAUUCAGUACUCCUGGAUGGGGCUCAUGGUGUUUGCCAUGGGCUGGCGAUCCUUCACCAAUGUCAACUCCAGGAUGCUCUACUUCGCCCCUGAUCUGGUUUUCAAUGAGUACCGCAUGCACAAGUCCCGGAUGUACAGCCAGUGUGUCCGAAUGAGGCACCUCUCUCAAGAGUUUGGAUGGCUCCAAAUCACCCCCCAGGAAUUCCUGUGCAUGAAAGCACUGCUACUCUUCAGCAUUAUUCCAGUGGAUGGGCUGAAAAAUCAAAAAUUCUUUGAUGAACUUCGAAUGAACUACAUCAAGGAACUCGAUCGUAUCAUUGCAUGCAAAAGAAAAAAUCCCACAUCCUGCUCAAGACGCUUCUACCAGCUCACCAAGCUCCUGGACUCCGUGCAGCCUAUUGCGAGAGAGCUGCAUCAGUUCACUUUUGACCUGCUAAUCAAGUCACACAUGGUGAGCGUGGACUUUCCGGAAAUGAUGGCAGAGAUCAUCUCUGUGCAAGUGCCCAAGAUCCUUUCUGGGAAAGUCAAGCCCAUCUAUUUCCACACCCAGUGAAGCAUUGGAAACCCUAUUUCCCCACCCCAGCUCAUGCCCCCUUUCAGAUGUCUUCUGCCUGUUAUAACUCUGCACUACUCCUCUGCAGUGCCUUGGGGAAUUUCCUCUAUUGAUGUACAGUCUGUCAUGAACAUGUUCCUGAAUUCUAUUUGCUGGGCUUUUUUUUUCUCUUUCUCUCCUUUCUUUUUCUUCUUCCCUCCCUAUCUAACCCUCCCAUGGCACCUUCAGACUUUGCUUCCCAUUGUGGCUCCUAUCUGUGUUUUGAAUGGUGUUGUAUGCCUUUAAAUCUGUGAUGAUCCUCAUAUGGCCCAGUGUCAAGUUGUGCUUGUUUACAGCACUACUCUGUGCCAGCCACACAAACGUUUACUUAUCUUAUGCCACGGGAAGUUUAGAGAGCUAAGAUUAUCUGGGGAAAUCAAAACAAAAACAAGCAAACAAAAAAAAAAAGCAAAAACAAAACAAAAAAUAAGCCAAAAAACCUUGCUAGUGUUUUUUCCUCAAAAAUAAAUAAAUAAAUAAAUAAAUACGUACAUACAUACACACAUACAUACAAACAUAUAGAAAUCCCCAAAGAGGCCAAUAGUGACGAGAAGGUGAAAAUUGCAGGCCCAUGGGGAGUUACUGAUUUUUUCAUCUCCUCCCUCCACGGGAGACUUUAUUUUCUGCCAAUGGCUAUUGCCAUUAGAGGGCAGAGUGACCCCAGAGCUGAGUUGGGCAGGGGGGUGGACAGAGAGGAGAGGACAAGGAGGGCAAUGGAGCAUCAGUACCUGCCCACAGCCUUGGUCCCUGGGGGCUAGACUGCUCAACUGUGGAGCAAUUCAUUAUACUGAAAAUGUGCUUGUUGUUGAAAAUUUGUCUGCAUGUUAAUGCCUCACCCCCAAACCCUUUUCUCUCUCACUCUCUGCCUCCAACUUCAGAUUGACUUUCAAUAGUUUUUCUAAGACCUUUGAACUGAAUGUUCUCUUCAGCCAAAACUUGGCGACUUCCACAGAAAAGUCUGACCACUGAGAAGAAGGAGAGCAGAGAUUUAACCCUUUGUAAGGCCCCAUUUGGAUCCAGGUCUGCUUUCUCAUGUGUGAGUCAGGGAGGAGCUGGAGCCAGAGGAGAAGAAAAUGAUAGCUUGGCUGUUCUCCUGCUUAGGACACUGACUGAAUAGUUAAACUCUCACUGCCACUACCUUUUCCCCACCUUUAAAAGACCUGAAUGAAGUUUUCUGCCAAACUCCGUGAAGCCACAAGCACCUUAUGUCCUCCCUUCAGUGUUUUGUGGGCCUGAAUUUCAUCACACUGCAUUUCAGCCAUGGUCAUCAAGCCUGUUUGCUUCUUUUGGGCAUGUUCACAGAUUCUCUGUUAAGAGCCCCCACCACCAAGAAGGUUAGCAGGCCAACAGCUCUGACAUCUAUCUGUAGAUGCCAGUAGUCACAAAGAUUUCUUACCAACUCUCAGAUCGCUGGAGCCCUUAGACAAACUGGAAAGAAGGCAUCAAAGGGAUCAGGCAAGCUGGGCGUCUUGCCCUUGUCCCCCAGAGAUGAUACCCUCCCAGCAAGUGGAGAAGUUCUCACUUCCUUCUUUAGAGCAGCUAAAGGGGCUACCCAGAUCAGGGUUGAAGAGAAAACUCAAUUACCAGGGUGGGAAGAAUGAAGGCACUAGAACCAGAAACCCUGCAAAUGCUCUUCUUGUCACCCAGCAUAUCCACCUGCAGAAGUCAUGAGAAGAGAGAAGGAACAAAGAGGAGACUCUGACUACUGAAUUAAAAUCUUCAGCGGCAAAGCCUAAAGCCAGAUGGACACCAUCUGGUGAGUUUACUCAUCAUCCUCCUCUGCUGCUGAUUCUGGGCUCUGACAUUGCCCAUACUCACUCAGAUUCCCCACCUUUGUUGCUGCCUCUUAGUCAGAGGGAGGCCAAACCAUUGAGACUUUCUACAGAACCAUGGCUUCUUUCGGAAAGGUCUGGUUGGUGUGGCUCCAAUACUUUGCCACCCAUGAACUCAGGGUGUGCCCUGGGACACUGGUUUUAUAUAGUCUUUUGGCACACCUGUGUUCUGUUGACUUCGUUCUUCAAGCCCAAGUGCAAGGGAAAAUGUCCACCUACUUUCUCAUCUUGGCCUCUGCCUCCUUACUUAGCUCUUAAUCUCAUCUGUUGAACUCAAGAAAUCAAGGGCCAGUCAUCAAGCUGCCCAUUUUAAUUGAUUCACUCUGUUUGUUGAGAGGAUAGUUUCUGAGUGACAUGAUAUGAUCCACAAGGGUUUCCUUCCCUGAUUUCUGCAUUGAUAUUAAUAGCCAAACGAACUUCAAAACAGCUUUAAAUAACAAGGGAGAGGGGAACCUAAGAUGAGUAAUAUGCCAAUCCAAGACUGCUGGAGAAAACUAAAGCUGACAGGUUCCCUUUUUGGGGUGGGAUAGACAUGUUCUGGUUUUCUUUAUUAUUACACAAUCUGGCUCAUGUACAGGAUCACUUUUAGCUGUUUUAAACAGAAAAAAAUAUCCACCACUCUUUUCAGUUACACUAGGUUACAUUUUAAUAGGUCCUUUACAUCUGUUUUGGAAUGAUUUUCAUCUUUUGUGAUACACAGAUUGAAUUAUAUCAUUUUCAUAUCUCUCCUUGUAAAUACUAGAAGCUCUCCUUUACAUUUCUCUAUCAAAUUUUUCAUCUUUAUGGGUUUCCCAAUUGUGACUCUUGUCUUCAUGAAUAUAUGUUUUUCAUUUGCAAAAGCCAAAAAUCAGUGAAACAGCAGUGUAAUUAAAAGCAACAACUGGAUUACUCCAAAUUUCCAAAUGACAAAACUAGGGAAAAAUAGCCUACACAAGCCUUUAGGCCUACUCUUUCUGUGCUUGGGUUUGAGUGAACAAAGGAGAUUUUAGCUUGGCUCUGUUCUCCCAUGGAUGAAAGGAGGAGGAUUUUUUUUUUCUUUUGGCCAUUGAUGUUCUAGCCAAUGUAAUUGACAGAAGUCUCAUUUUGCAUGCGCUCUGCUCUACAAACAGAGUUGGUAUGGUUGGUAUACUGUACUCACCUGUGAGGGACUGGCCACUCAGACCCACUUAGCUGGUGAGCUAGAAGAUGAGGAUCACUCACUGGAAAAGUCACAAGGACCAUCUCCAAACAAGUUGGCAGUGCUCGAUGUGGACGAAGAGUGAGGAAGAGAAAAAGAAGGAGCACCAGGGAGAAGGCUCCGUCUGUGCUGGGCAGCAGACAGCUGCCAGGAUCACGAACUCUGUAGUCAAAGAAAAGAGUCGUGUGGCAGUUUCAGCUCUCGUUCAUUGGGCAGCUCGCCUAGGCCCAGCCUCUGAGCUGACAUGGGAGUUGUUGGAUUCUUUGUUUCAUAGCUUUUUCUAUGCCAUAGGCAAUAUUGUUGUUCUUGGAAAGUUUAUUAUUUUUUUAACUCCCUUACUCUGAGAAAGGGAUAUUUUGAAGGACUGUCAUAUAUCUUUGAAAAAAGAAAAUCUGUAAUACAUAUAUUUUUAUGUAUGUUCACUGGCACUAAAAAAUAUAGAGAGCUUCAUUCUGUCCUUUGGGUAGUUGCUGAGGUAAUUGUCCAGGUUGAAAAAUAAUGUGCUGAUGCUAGAGUCCCUCUCUGUCCAUACUCUACUUCUAAAUACAUAUAGGCAUACAUAGCAAGUUUUAUUUGACUUGUACUUUAAGAGAAAAUAUGUCCACCAUCCACAUGAUGCACAAAUGAGCUAACAUUGAGCUUCAAGUAGCUUCUAAGUGUUUGUUUCAUUAGGCACAGCACAGAUGUGGCCUUUCCCCCCUUCUCUCCCUUGAUAUCUGGCAGGGCAUAAAGGCCCAGGCCACUUCCUCUGCCCCUUCCCAGCCCUGCACCAAAGCUGCAUUUCAGGAGACUCUCUCCAGACAGCCCAGUAACUACCCGAGCAUGGCCCCUGCAUAGCCCUGGAAAAAUAAGAGGCUGACUGUCUACGAAUUAUCUUGUGCCAGUUGCCCAGGUGAGAGGGCACUGGGCCAAGGGAGUGGUUUUCAUGUUUGACCCACUACAAGGGGUCAUGGGAAUCAGGAAUGCCAAAGCACCAGAUCAAAUCCAAAACUUAAAGUCAAAAUAAGCCAUUCAGCAUGUUCAGUUUCUUGGAAAAGGAAGUUUCUACCCCUGAUGCCUUUGUAGGCAGAUCUGUUCUCACCAUUAAUCUUUUUGAAAAUCUUUUAAAGCAGUUUUUAAAAAGAGAGAUGAAAGCAUCACAUUAUAUAACCAAAGAUUACAUUGUACCUGCUAAGAUACCAAAAUUCAUAAGGGCAGGGGGGGAGCAAGCAUUAGUGCCUCUUUGAUAAGCUGUCCAAAGACAGACUAAAGGACUCUGCUGGUGACUGACUUAUAAGAGCUUUGUGGGUUUUUUUUUCCCUAAUAAUAUACAUGUUUAGAAGAAUUGAAAAUAAUUUCGGGAAAAUGGGAUUAUGGGUCCUUCACUAAGUGAUUUUAUAAGCAGAACUGGCUUUCCUUUUCUCUAGUAGUUGCUGAGCAAAUUGUUGAAGCUCCAUCAUUGCAUGGUUGGAAAUGGAGCUGUUCUUAGCCACUGUGUUUGCUAGUGCCCAUGUUAGCUUAUCUGAAGAUGUGAAACCCUUGCUGAUAAGGGAGCAUUUAAAGUACUAGAUUUUGCACUAGAGGGACAGCAGGCAGAAAUCCUUAUUUCUGCCCACUUUGGAUGGCACAAAAAGUUAUCUGCAGUUGAAGGCAGAAAGUUGAAAUACAUUGUAAAUGAAUAUUUGUAUCCAUGUUUCAAAAUUGAAAUAUAUAUAUAUAUAUAUAUAUAUAUAUAUAUAUAUAUAUAGUGUGUGUGUGUGUUCUGAUAGCUUUAACUUUCUCUGCAUCUUUAUAUUUGGUUCCAGAUCACACCUGAUGCCAUGUACUUGUGAGAGAGGAUGCAGUUUUGUUUUGGAAGCUCUCUCAGAACAAACAAGACACCUGGAUUGAUCAGUUAACUAAAAGUUUUCUCCCCUAUUGGGUUUGACCCACAGGUCCUGUGAAGGAGCAGAGGGAUAAAAAGAGUAGAGGACAUGAUACAUUGUACUUUACUAGUUCAAGACAGAUGAAUGUGGAAAGCAUAAAAACUCAAUGGAACUGACUGAGAUUUACCACAGGGAAGGCCCAAACUUGGGGCCAAAAGCCUACCCAAGUGAUUGACCAGUGGCCCCCUAAUGGGACCUGAGCUGUUGGAAGAAGAGAACUGUUCCUUGGUCUUCACCAUCCUUGUGAGAGAAGGGCAGUUUCCUGCAUUGGAACCUGGAGCAAGCGCUCUAUCUUUCACACAAAUUCCCUCACCUGAGAUUGAGGUGCUCUUGUUACUGGGUGUCUGUGUGCUGUAAUUCUGGUUUUGGAUAUGUUCUGUAAAGAUUUUGACAAAUGAAAAUGUGUUUUUCUCUGUUAAAACUUGUCAGAGUACUAGAAGUUGUAUCUCUGUAGGUGCAGGUCCAUUUCUGCCCACAGGUAGGGUGUUUUUCUUUGAUUAAGAGAUUGACACUUCUGUUGCCUAGGACCUCCCAACUCAACCAUUUCUAGGUGAAGGCAGAAAAAUCCACAUUAGUUACUCCUCUUCAGACAUUUCAGCUGAGAUAACAAAUCUUUUGGAAUUUUUUCACCCAUAGAAAGAGUGGUAGAUAUUUGAAUUUAGCAGGUGGAGUUUCAUAGUAAAAACAGCUUUUGACUCAGCUUUGAUUUAUCCUCAUUUGAUUUGGCCAGAAAGUAGGUAAUAUGCAUUGAUUGGCUUCUGAUUCCAAUUCAGUAUAGCAAGGUGCUAGGUUUUUUCCUUUCCCCACCUGUCUCUUAGCCUGGGGAAUUAAAUGAGAAGCCUUAGAAUGGGUGGCCCUUGUGACCUGAAACACUUCCCACAUAAGCUACUUAACAAGAUUGUCAUGGAGCUGCAGAUUCCAUUGCCCACCAAAGACUAGAACACACACAUAUCCAUACACCAAAGGAAAGACAAUUCUGAAAUGCUGUUUCUCUGGUGGUUCCCUCUCUGGCUGCUGCCUCACAGUAUGGGAACCUGUACUCUGCAGAGGUGACAGGCCAGAUUUGCAUUAUCUCACAACCUUAGCCCUUGGUGCUAACUGUCCUACAGUGAAGUGCCUGGGGGGUUGUCCUAUCCCAUAAGCCACUUGGAUGCUGACAGCAGCCACCAUCAGAAUGACCCACGCAAAAAAAAGAAAAAAAAAAUUAAAAAGUCCCCUCACAACCCAGUGACACCUUUCUGCUUUCCUCUAGACUGGAACAUUGAUUAGGGAGUGCCUCAGACAUGACAUUCUUGUGCUGUCCUUGGAAUUAAUCUGGCAGCAGGAGGGAGCAGACUAUGUAAACAGAGAUAAAAAUUAAUUUUCAAUAUUGAAGGAAAAAAGAAAUAAGAAGAGAGAGAGAAAGAAAGCAUCACACAAAGAUUUUCUUAAAAGAAACAAUUUUGCUUGAAAUCUCUUUAGAUGGGGCUCAUUUCUCACGGUGGCACUUGGCCUCCACUGGGCAGCAGGACCAGCUCCAAGCGCUAGUGUUCUGUUCUCUUUUUGUAAUCUUGGAAUCUUUUGUUGCUCUAAAUACAAUUAAAAAUGGCAGAAACUUGUUUGUUGGACUACAUGUGUGACUUUGGGUCUGUCUCUGCCUCUGCUUUCAGAAAUGUCAUCCAUUGUGUAAAAUAUUGGCUUACUGGUCUGCCAGCUAAAACUUGGCCACAUCCCCUGUUAUGGCUGCAGGAUCGAGUUAUUGUUAACAAAGAGACCCAAGAAAAGCUGCUAAUGUCCUCUUAUCAUUGUUGUUAAUUUGUUAAAACAUAAAGAAAUCUAAAAUUUCA